GUGCCCUCGCGCGACGCGAAGGUUGUCGGGAUCCGCGGCAGCAGCGGCUGCUUGAGAUCUGUUUCUGGGGCCUCUGGCGGUGGCGGCCUGGGGCGGCGCGACGGCUGGUGCGCAGGUACACUGAUGCUGAAGUACUAUGAGCCUUCGGAACUUGUGGAGAGACUACAAAGUUUUGGUUGUUAUGGUCCCUUUAGUUGGGCUCAUACAUUUGGGGUGGUACAGAAUCAAAAGCAGCCCUGUUUUCCAAAUACCUAAAAACGACGACAUUCCUGAGCAAGAUAGUCUGGGACUUUCAAAUCUUCAGAAGAGCCAAAUCCAGGGGAAGUAGCAGGCUUGCAAUCUUCAGGUAAAGAAGCAGCUUUGAAUCUGAGCUUCAUAUCGAAAGAAGAGAUGAAAAAUACCAGUUGGAUUAGAAAGAACUGGCUUCUUGUAGCUGGGAUAUCUUUCAUAGGUGUCCAUCUUGGAACAUACUUUUUGCAGAGGUCUGCAAAGCAGUCUGUAAAAUUUCAGUCUCAAAGCAAACAAAAGAGUAUUGAAGAGUGAAGUAAAAUAAAUAUUUGGAAUUACUAA